AGUCCCUCAGUUUGCCCGGCACCGGAGGAGGGUCGGGCGGCAUCUUCCGGGUACUGGGGCUCUGCGGAGCGGAGAAGAGGUUCCAGCGGGGAAUGGUAUAUCUGGAUUCAAGAAGCCGCGGCUCGGCGCCAGAUCCUGGAGUGUAGAUAUUUGGGGGGAGGGGAGAGCUAGAGGGAGCGAGCGAGCGAGCGCCAGAGAGAGGCAGCGCGCAGCGCGCACGGACGGGGGGCUGCUGCGCGGAGAAGAUGUAAGCGCGUGGGGUCUCGCUGGCCUCUGAGCACCAUGCAGAAGGGGAUCCGGCUGAAUGAUGGCCACGUCGCGUCCCUGGGACUGCUGGCGCGCAAGGACGGCACGCGCAAAGGCUACCUGAGCAAGCGGAGUUCGGACAACACAAAAUGGCAAACCAAGUGGUUCGCGCUGCUGCAGAACCUGCUCUUCUACUUCGAGAGCGACUCGAGCUCGCGGCCCUCGGGGCUUUACCUGCUGGAGGGCUGCGUCUGCGACCGCGCGCCCUCCCCCAAGCCGGCGCUGUCGGCCAAGGAGCCGCUGGAGAAACAGCAUUACUUCACGGUGAACUUCAGCCAUGAGAACCAGAAAGCCUUGGAGCUGAGGACAGAGGACGCAAAAGAUUGUGACGAAUGGGUGGCAGCCAUUGCACAUGCCAGCUACAGGACCCUCGCCACAGAGCAUGAGGCAUUAAUGCAGAAAUACCUGCACCUGCUGCAGAUCGUGGAGACAGAGAAGACCGUGGCCAAGCAGCUUCGGCAGCAGAUCGAGGAUGGGGAGAUCGAGAUCGAGCGGCUGAAGGCAGAGAUCACAUCCCUGCUCAAGGACAAUGAGCGCAUCCAGUCCACCCAGACUGUCGCCCCCAACGAUGAAGACAGCGACAUCAAGAAAAUUAAGAAGGUGCAGAGCUUCCUGCGGGGCUGGCUGUGCCGGCGGAAGUGGAAGACCAUCAUCCAGGACUACAUCCGGUCACCCCAUGCUGACAGCAUGCGCAAGAGGAACCAGGUGGUGUUCAGCAUGCUGGAGGCUGAGGCUGAGUACGUGCAGCAGCUGCACAUCCUUGUCAACAAUUUCCUGCGCCCGCUGCGGAUGGCCGCCAGCUCCAAGAAGCCUCCCAUCACACACGACGACGUCAGCAGCAUCUUCCUGAACAGCGAAACCAUCAUGUUUUUACAUCAGAUCUUUUACCAAGGCCUGAAGGCCCGCAUCUCCAGCUGGCCCACGCUGGUCCUGGCUGACCUAUUUGACAUCCUGCUGCCCAUGCUCAACAUCUACCAAGAGUUCGUCCGCAACCACCAGUACAGCCUGCAGAUCCUGGCCCACUGCAAGCAGAACCGUGACUUCGACAAGCUGCUGAAGCACUACGAGGCCAAGCCUGACUGCGAGGAGAGGACGCUGGAGACCUUCCUCACCUACCCCAUGUUCCAGAUCCCCAGGUACAUCCUGACCCUCCAUGAGCUCCUGGCCCACACGCCUCAUGAGCACGUUGAGCGCAACAGCCUGGACUACGCCAAGUCCAAACUGGAGGAGCUGUCCAGAAUAAUGCACGAUGAAGUAAGUGAGACGGAGAACAUCCGGAAAAACCUGGCCAUCGAGCGCAUGAUCAUCGAAGGCUGUGAGAUCCUCCUGGACACCAGCCAGACCUUUGUGAGACAAGGUUCCCUCAUUCAGGUGCCCAUGUCUGAAAAGGGCAAGAUCACCAGGGGGCGCCUGGGGUCUCUCUCCCUAAAGAAAGAGGGCGAGCGACAGUGCUUCCUGUUUUCUAAGCAUCUGAUUAUCUGUACCAGAGGCUCUGGAGGGAAGCUUCACUUGACCAAGAAUGGAGUCAUAUCCCUCAUUGACUGCACUUUAUUGGAGGAGCCAGAAAGCACGGAGGAGGAAGCCAAAGGAUCCGGCCAAGACAUAGAUCACUUGGAUUUUAAAAUCGGGGUGGAGCCAAAGGAUUCCCCGCCCUUUACAGUCAUCCUAGUGGCCUCGUCCAGACAGGAGAAGGCAGCGUGGACCAGUGACAUCAGCCAGUGUGUGGAUAACAUCCGAUGCAAUGGGCUCAUGAUGAACGCAUUUGAAGAAAAUUCCAAGGUCACUGUGCCGCAGAUGAUCAAGAGGACCAGGGAGGGGACCAGGGAAGCAGAAAUGAGCAGGUCCGACGCCUCCUUAUAUUGUGAUGAUGUUGACAUUCGCUUCAGCAAAACCAUGAACUCCUGCAAAGUGCUGCAGAUCCGCUACGCCAGUGUGGAGCGGCUGCUGGAGAGGCUGACGGACCUGCGCUUCCUGAGCAUCGACUUCCUCAACACCUUCCUGCACUCCUACCGCGUCUUCACCACCGCCAUCGUGGUCCUGGACAAGCUCAUUACCAUCUACAAGAAGCCUAUCAGUGCCAUUCCUGCCAGGUGGCUGAGGUCGCUGGAGCUCCUGUUUGCCAGUGGCCAGAACAAUAAGCUCCUGUACGGUGAACCCCCCAAGUCCCCGCGCGCCACCCGCAAGUUCUCCUCGCCGCCACCUCUGUCCAUCACCAAGACAUCGUCACCGAGCCGCCGGCGGAAGCUCUCCCUGAACAUCCCCAUCAUCACUGGCGGCAAGGCCCUGGACCUGGCCGCCCUCAGCUGCAACUCCAAUGGCUACACCAGCAUGUACUCGGCCAUGUCACCCUUCAGCAAGGCCACGCUGGACACCAGCAAGCUCUAUGUGUCCAGCAGCUUCACCAACAAGAUUCCAGAUGAGGGCGAUACGACCCCUGAGAAGCCCGAAGACCCUUCAGCGCUCAGCAAGCAGAGCUCAGAAGUCUCCAUGAGAGAGGAGUCAGAUAUUGAUCAAAACCAGAGUGAUGAUGGUGAUACUGAAACAUCACCAACUAAAUCUCCAACAACACCCAAAUCAGUCAAAAACAAAAAUUCUUCAGAGUUCCCACUCUUUUCCUAUAACAAUGGAGUCGUCAUGACCUCCUGUCGUGAACUGGACAAUAACCGCAGUGCCUUGUCGGCCGCCUCUGCCUUUGCCAUAGCAACCGCCGGGGCCAACGAGGGCACCCCAAACAAGGAGAAGUACCGGAGGAUGUCCUUAGCCAGUGCAGGGUUUCCCCCAGACCAGAGGAAUGGAGACAAGGAGUUUGUGAUCCGCAGAGCAGCCACCAAUCGUGUCUUGAACGUGCUCCGCCACUGGGUGUCCAAGCACUCUCAGGACUUUGAGACCAACGAUGAGCUCAAAUGCAAGGUGAUCGGCUUCCUGGAAGAAGUCAUGCACGACCCGGAGCUCCUGACCCAGGAGCGGAAGGCUGCAGCCAACAUCAUCAGGACUCUGACCCAGGAGGACCCAGGUGACAACCAGAUCACGCUGGAGGAGAUCACGCAGAUGGCUGAAGGCGUGAAGGCUGAGCCCUUUGAAAACCACUCAGCCCUGGAGAUCGCGGAGCAGCUGACCCUGCUAGAUCACCUCGUCUUCAAGAAGAUUCCUUAUGAGGAGUUCUUCGGACAAGGAUGGAUGAAACUGGAAAAGAAUGAAAGGACCCCUUAUAUCAUGAAAACCACUAAGCACUUCAAUGACAUCAGUAACUUGAUUGCUUCAGAAAUCAUCCGCAAUGAGGACAUCAACGCCAGGGUGAGCGCCAUCGAGAAGUGGGUGGCCGUAGCUGACAUAUGCCGCUGCCUCCACAACUACAAUGCCGUACUGGAGAUCACCUCGUCCAUGAACCGCAGUGCAAUCUUCCGGCUCAAAAAGACGUGGCUCAAAGUCUCUAAGCAGACUAAAGCUUUGAUUGAUAAGCUCCAAAAGCUUGUGUCAUCUGAGGGCAGAUUUAAGAAUCUCAGAGAAGCUCUGAAAAAACAGAUGUUGCACCCAUCUGUGCUGUCCAGCCGUCUCUCUUCUGCCUGGGCUCCCGAGAGCCCCUGUGGACUGUGCUUGUGGGGAGCUGCCCCCUCCGUGCAUUCACCAACUUGUCCGUCCGUCCGCCCCCGGGGCACCACUCCAUCCACCUCCUCACAUGGCUGGCUUCCUCGUCUGCCGCCGCCACCACCGCUGCCUCCACUGCCUCUGGGGCCCCCCAUUCUGUCUGAGUCCCCACCCUGACCGUCUUCCCUCUUUCAGGUGGCCUGUGGGCCCGUGUAAGUGUCUCUCCCACAUUCCCCUGCUCCCUGCAGCACAGGGCAGAGGUGGCCUGCGGGCCUCUGGAAGCUAAGAGCUUUAUGCAAACCAGGUUCUGGACUUGCAGAGACAUAGGCAGGGCACACAGAGGAGGGAGGGACUGGGGAAACCUGGGGCAAAUGCUUCCCGCACCCCCUCUCCUGAGGCUCUAAGGUUUUCACAAAGAGCGGUGUUGCAUGAAUACUGAGCGUCUGUUUCACUAGGCAGGGGACGGGGGCAAGAGUAGCGAGGUGGCAGUCCAUGGGCAUAGCCAAUGACCUCCCCAGAGAAGGAGUCCUGCUAUGGGCCUCACCAUGUUGGUCUGCAGCCCAUUCAUACGUCCCAGGCAUCUUUUUUUAGCUUUUCAUUAAGAUAUCCAAUUCGGGCUAGGCACAGUGGCUCAUGCCUAUAAUCCCAGCACUUUAGGAGGCCGAGGUGGGCAGAUCACUUGAGGUCAGGAGCUAGAAACCAACCUUGCCAACAUGGCAAAACCCUGUCUCUACUGAAAAUACAAAAAUUAGCCAGGCGUGGUGGCACAUGCCUAUAAUCCCAGCUACUUGGGAGGCUGAAGCACGAGAAUCGCUUGAGCCCAGGAGGCAGAAGUUGCAGCGAGCUGAGAUCGUGCCACUGCACUCCAGUCUAGGUGACAGAACAAGACUGUCUCAAAAAAAAAAAAAAAAAAAAAAAACAAAAGAAAAGAAAAAGAAAAAGAAGAAAAAAUAUCCAAUUUCUGCCAGCAUCCAGGCUGGAGAAUGGCCUUAUUGCAUUUCCCAGCCGAGACUUCACCACCAAACACCCCACUAGCCACUCUCUUAAAUGUCCCUUGCCCCACCUGCAACAGCCCUAACUAUGUGUGCCCCUUCAGUCCCUGCCAGAUGCCCUGAGAGUGGCCUCAUCUCCCCUUCUCAUUCCCCAAGCCUACAUACUGGCAAAGUCCUAUGCCUGUUCCCUCCUCCCAACCUCCCAGCAAUCGGAACCUUCCCCCAGCUCCAGGCAACAAGAAUUUGGUUGAAAACUGAAUUUAGUAGCAAAAUGUGGUCACCAGCAUUUUUGGGGCCGAUUCCAGUUUUGACUACCCUGUCUAAUCUCAACCGAGCACACACUUGCAUAUCUGCACCUUUUGUGUUUAAUUUGAAUAGGAAGCCCUUGAUUUAGAGGAACACGGGGGACAGGCUGUUAUUGUAGGCUGCUGCAGUGAAAGCCUUUCCCCUUUGUUCCCCUGAAUUAAGGAUGGGAACAGCCAUGGAGGAGCGUGUCAGCUAGCUGACUGCCAGGCCAUCCCCUAUACCCUUUAAUCAGGGUGAGAAUCAAUUUAUCUACAUGGAUGUCAUGAGCCCAAAGGCUGAGCUCUAGAGUCUCAGGGGUUCCAGCAAAGCCAAGUAUCUAUCUCUAUCUUUAUUCUCUGCCUGUGACCACAGAGCAGCCUAGCAACCCAGUGGUAAAAUGGGACUUUCCACCCCCACCCCAUCGCAGUUUUGUUUUUCAAAGACUACUUACCUGAUCACCCUGUACCUCGUGCCAGAACCUUGGACCCUGGCCCCAGGGGAUUCAGCCCACACAGCCCAGCCUCAAGGGCCCUCAUGCCCUCCCUGAAUGCCCUUCCCCAGGCCUCAAGAUGGGAGAGAGGAGAUCCCCAACCACAGCCGGCAGAAACUUGUAAGAGAGAAUAGCCCAUCCCACAGCCAGGGCAGUACAGGGAAGAGAGAAGUUGGAGAGAAAGAGGAAGGGGAGGUGGACUCAUUGCUUGUCUCGGGUUGGUUUCCUGGAGUUUGGUGUAGAGCAUGGGCAGCUGCCUCUUGCCAGCAGCAGCUGGUCCCCCAUAAUCUCCCUUAUUCCAUUUAACAUCAUCAGGAGCGUCUUGGUGGAAAGAAACAUCCAGUUUGGGGGCUCCAAACAACCACAGGCAAGGCCAGGUGUCACCAGCAUGGGAGUGCGACAGCGAGGCCUUGCCCAGAAACCAGAAGCAGCUUUCAGGCUAGGGGUGGGACACUUUCCUCUCUGCUCCCUAAAAUGCUAGCUGCAGGCCCGUGAGGGCUCUGCCAGAAGAGGAAGCCACCCCCGUAUCAGCUCUGCUUGAUAGGCCCUGCCAAGGGCAAGACUGGACCUCACCCGAGAGAGGCCAAAAGGCCAAUAUGGAAGGUUCAGGACUUGCCUGUUGUUGGGUGUCUUGCCUGCAGGAAGCCCCAACAUGCUUCCCUUUUCAUUCAGAGGCUCGGUGUGGCUCAGUCCCUAUGCCGUGUGUCCCUGUGGGGCCCUCCAGCAGUCCUCUGUCCCAAUCUGGCAACUCCAUACAUUUGCCCACAUGGCUCUGGAUUUCGGAUGGGUGUGUGUGUGUGUGUGUGUGUGUGUUUGAUUGAGUGUUCUCUUGUCCCCUCCUUCAUGGCCCCUCACUAUAGAGCAAGCUUGUCCAACCCGUGGCCUAAGGGCCGCAUAUGGCCCAGGAUGGUUUUAAAUGCAGCCCAACACAAAUUGGUAAACUUUCUUAAAACAUUAAGAGAUUUUUUUGUGAUUUUUUUCCAGCUUAUUAGCUAUCGUUAGUGUGUUAGUGUAUUUUACGUGUGGCCCAAGACAAUUCUUCUUCCAAUGCGGCCAGGGAAGCGAAAAGAUUGGCCACCCCUGCCAUAGAGGUAGUAAAUAGGGACAGAGGUUAGUACUGGGGCUGGGCGUGCUACUUGCAAGUGAUUCGAUUGCAAAUCCACCACCUUCCCACAGCUGAACCAUGACUCCCCAUAAAUACCAGGGGAAGUCGACCCUCAGUGAUCAGAGGACCUCUGAUCCUUUUCACUGAUCUGGGUGGUCAGAAACCCCCAAAAGCCUUGAGAAACACUCUGAGUCCUUUGGUCAUUUGCAGUCAGCUUGCAGUCACCAGGCCUCCCGUUCUCCCUUCCAUCCUUAGAGCACUCCACGGCUACCUGGCUACUGUCACACAUGCAGGGUGAAGGGGGAGAGCACCUCUCAGAACCCACCGGUCAGCACUGCCACAGCCUUACGACUCCAGAGUUACUUCUCAGAUCUUUGGAUUAUUUCUCCAUCAGACUCAUAAGCCUGGGCUUCAGACUUGGAGUAUGAUAGAAAGGAAAUGAAGAGCUGGCCGGGCACAGUGGCUCACACCUGUAAUCUGAGCACUUUGGGAAGCUGAGGCGAGCAGAUCACUUGAGCUUAGGAGUUCUAGACCAGCCUGGGCAACAUGGCAAAAAUACAAAAUUUCUGUCCCUACCAAAAAUACAAAAAUUCGCUGGGUAUGGUGGUGCAUGCAUGUAGUCCAGCUACUUAGGAGGCUGAGGCAGGAGGACCAUUGGAGCCUGAGAAGUCAAGGCUGCAGUGAGCUGUGAUUGUGCCACUGCACUCCAGUCUAGGUAACAGAGUGAGACCCUGCCUCAAAAAAAAAAAAAAGAAAAAGAAAGGAAGGAAAUGAAGACCUGUGCAUGUAAUAAUCAUGGACUGGAAGGGAUGGAAGGAUGCAAAGCAGCCCCUCCAGUGGCUGGAUGCUCCUUACUCUUUUCUUUUUUUUUUUAAUCACAAAGCACAGUAAAUAUAUAUAUUUGAAACUACAAGCCUGUAUACAAAUGCAUAUAUGCAUCACAGGAACAAAAAUUCCACAAAACAAUAUAUACCUUUAUUUCAUUUGAUGAAGUCAGAUAUUUUCUUUUUCACUUGUUAUUUUUAUUUGUUUUCAAUUAAAUAGAGAUGGGGUCUCACUAUGUUGCUCAGGCUGGUCUUGAACCGUUGGACUCAAGUGAUCCUCCCACCUCAACCUCUCAAAUCCCACUGCCUGGGAUUACAGGAGUGAGCCACCACUCGGCCCUUUUUCACUUUUUAAAAAUUCUGGUCUACACCUUCUAAAUUGAUUUCAACACCCAUGAAAGGGUCAGCCCUACAUUUGGAAAAACACUUCUGUCUGCUGUGUCCCUAACGCCAGGCCUCUGCCUCCUUCACGACUUUGCCAUACUGUGCCAACUGUAUUUGUGUUUACCUAACAGCCUCUUUAAAUUAAUUCACUUUUUCCCAAAAAGAAAUAAGAAGGAAAUUUUGUAUCAUGGCAAAUGGAAAACCAGCUUACUUGCUGUAAAUACAAGAAUGCCAUUUAAAAAUAUAUGGUAAAAACAAAAUAAUGUUUUUGAAUUCUGGCCAAAUACUGAUGUUUGCCAACACUCUGAUUCUGACACCUGUUGCUAUUUGUCUAAAAAGAGAAAAUGUGAAAGGAGGAGAAUGGCAAGUAUCAAAAGUGUCAAAGUCACACUAUCACCAAAUGAGGCGCUCUCCCUGAGCAGAAGGGAAAAAAGUAAAAAUCCAAUGUUUCUUACCA